CCUCGCUUCCUCCGCGGUCUUCCGAGCGGUCGCGUGAACUGCUUCCUGCAGGCUGGCCAUGGCGCUUCACGUUCCCAAGGCUCCGGGCUUUGCCCAGAUGCUCAAGGAGGGAGCGAAAGUAAGGGCUGAAGGAAAGGAAUGAGGUGGGAGCGUCAGCAUAGGGCUGCGGCGGCCGCGGCGAAGUAGGAGGGCCUACUAACGGGCUGAGCGUGCUGCCCUGGCUCAGCGGCCGGGGGAAGAGAAGAUUCCAGAAAGGGAGGUGAUUUUGGAAGGGCUCGGCCACCGGAGCCUGCGGGCACUUCUCUUCUUCCGCGACCGGGAGAAGGCCGAGGGAUCGGCGGCACGAUCGACAUUGUACACCUUGAAGGUGGACGGAUGUGAAGCCGCGCGUUGUAGGGCUGAAGCUUACCAAAGAAAGGAAGAAUGCACUUUUCAGGAUUAGAAGAGGCUGUGUAUAGAAACAUACAAGCUUGCAAGGAGCUUGCCCAAACCACUCGUACAGCAUAUGGACCAAAUGGAAUGAACAAAAUGGUUAUCAACCACUUGGAGAAGUUGUUUGUGACAAACGAUGCAGCAACUAUUUUAAGAGAACUAGAAGUACAGCAUCCUGCUGCAAAAAUGAUUGUAAUGGCUUCUCAUAUGCAAGAGCAAGAAGUUGGAGAUGGCACAAACUUUGUUCUGGUAUUUGCUGGAGCUCUCCUGGAAUUAGCUGAAGAACUUCUGAGGAUUGGCCUGUCAGUUUCAGAGGUCAUAGAAGGUUAUGAAAUAGCCUGCAGAAAAGCUCAUGAGAUUCUUCCUAAUUUGGUAUGUUGUUCUGCAAAAAACCUUCGAGAUAUUGAUGAAGUCUCAUCUCUACUUCGUACCUCCAUAAUGAGUAAACAAUAUGGUAAUGAAGUAUUUCUGGCCAAGCUUAUUGCUCAGGCAUGCGUAUCUAUUUUUCCUGAUUCCGGCCAUUUCAAUGUUGAUAACAUCAGAGUUUGUAAAAUUCUGGGCUCUGGUAUCAGUUCCUCUUCAGUAUUGCAUGGCAUGGUUUUUAAGAAGGAAACCGAAGGUGAUGUAACAUCUGUCAAAGAUGCAAAAAUAGCAGUGUACUCUUGUCCUUUUGAUGGCAUGAUAACAGAAACUAAGGGAACAGUGUUGAUAAAGACUGCUGAAGAAUUGAUGAAUUUUAGUAAGGGAGAAGAAAACCUCAUGGAUGCACAAGUCAAAGCUAUUGCUGAUACUGGUGCAAAUGUCGUAGUAACAGGUGGCAAAGUGGCAGACAUGGCUCUUCAUUAUGCAAAUAAAUAUAAUAUCAUGUUAGUGAGGCUAAACUCAAAAUGGGAUCUCCGAAGACUUUGUAAAACUGUUGGUGCUACAGCUCUUCCUAGAUUGACACCUCCUGUCCUUGAAGAAAUGGGACACUGUGACAGUGUUUACCUCUCAGAAGUUGGAGAUACUCAGGUGGUGGUUUUUAAGCAUGAAAAGGAAGAUGGCGCCAUUUCUACCAUAGUACUUCGAGGCUCUACAGACAAUCUGAUGGAUGACAUAGAAAGGGCAGUAGACGAUGGUGUUAAUACUUUCAAAGUUCUUACAAGGGAUAAACGUCUUGUACCCGGAGGUGGAGCAACAGAAAUUGAAUUAGCCAAACAGAUCACAUCAUAUGGAGAGACAUGUCCUGGACUUGAACAGUAUGCUAUUAAGAAGUUUGCUGAGGCAUUUGAAGCUAUUCCCCGCGCACUGGCAGAAAACUCUGGAGUUAAGGCCAAUGAAGUAAUCUCUAAACUUUAUGCAGUACAUCAAGAAGGAAAUAAAAACGUUGGAUUAGAUAUUGAGGCUGAAGUCCCUGCUGUAAAGGACAUGCUGGAAGCUGGUAUUCUAGAUACUUACCUGGGAAAAUAUUGGGCUAUCAAACUCGCUACUAAUGCUGCAGUCACUGUACUUAGAGUGGAUCAGAUCAUCAUGGCAAAACCAGCUGGUGGGCCCAAGCCUCCAAGUGGGAAGAAAGACUGGGAUGAUGACCAAAAUGAUUGAAAUUGGCUUAAUUUUUACUGUAGGUGAAGGCUGUAUUUGUAGUAGUACUCAAGAAUCACCUGAUGUUUUCUUAUUCUCCUUAAAUUAAGAGUUAUUUUGUGUUUGUAUUCUUGGCUGGAUGUUAUAAUAAACAUAUUGUUACUGUCAAA